AUCCCUCUCUUUCCUUCUCAGUUUGUGACUGACCCAGCAGCCCCGUCCCCCGUCUGCCACAAGCAGUCCACCUCCUGGUGCUGUGUGCUGCGUGCCAGCCGCUGCUCCCGCUGAGUGGAGACUCUGGCACCAGUGCCCACUGCGCUCUGCCUGCCGGUGGUGUCUGGAUUUCUAUAGGAAUCCCAGGAGGGUCUUACUGGAGGGUUGAGAGCCACCUGAUUGAAGGCGUUUGCAGUCAGAGUAAAGACGGCUGCCGCAGCAUGAACCCCUGAGCUGAUGAGUCUUAUUAUAGCCCGGCUGGCGGAAGACAGAGUGCUGCUAUUCACCUCUGCGUGGGCGUCGGUGGUGCAGGGGGAAGCAGCAGGCCAUCCAGCGGCUCACACCCUACGCGGCUGCAGCUGCCAAGGGCCUGGCCCCUGCCUCCCUCGGGCCAUGGUGAGCUGUGGCGGGGCUAGAGGAACCGGGACCCAGGUGAGGGGAGCCUCCAGGGACAGGUGACAGUUGUGGCCUGUGACCUCACUCUGCUCACCUCGGAGAGAUGACCUCAGUUUCUCCACCCAUAACUCAAGGAAUGCCCAGAUGGGAGACCAGGUUGCCAUGAAAACAUCUGAGUGAUCAACAUACUCGGGAGGCAACAAGAAGGCAGAUGAGGCUGGGUAGGCCCAUGGGUGCACCCCCAGCUUUGCGGCACUGUGCCCGACCCUCGGGCUCCUGGAAAGCCGAAGCCUGCCCCGCCCCCAUCCCAGGGGCUUGAAGGCUUCCUGGCUCCUCUUCUUCCCCCACCCAGGGAAUCAUAACUGAGAGGAACAGGAGAGGGCAUGAGGAGUGUAAAGAGACACCCGGGCCCUCUCCCUAACCCCUGGGCUGGAACGGGGCUCCCGCGCCUGCCUGUGCUCAGUGCUCCUCCCUCCCUCAGGACUGACAGGCGGCGCACCCAGGGGCUCCUCUCUCCCCAGAGCGACAGGGCCCGGAGAGCCGUGGGCCUCACCAUGCUGGCGCCGGGCAGCAGCCCUGGGCAGAGGGGCAGGCUCGCCCUGCAGUGGAGGCAAGUCUCCUGGAUCACCUGCUGGAUCGCCCUGUAUGCUGUGGAGGCCCUCCCCACCUGCCCUUUCUCCUGCAAGUGUGACAGCCGCAGCCUGGAGGUGGACUGCAGUGGCCUUGGCCUCACCACGGUGCCCCCAGACGUGCCCGCAGCCACCCGAACCCUCUUGCUCUUGAACAAUAAGCUGAGUGCCCUGCCAAGCUGGGCUUUCGCCAACCUCUCCAGCCUGCAGCGGUUGGACCUGUCCAACAACUUCCUGGACCGGCUGCCCCGCUCCAUUUUCGGGGACCUGACGAAUCUGACUGAGCUUCAGCUGCGCAAUAACAGCAUCAGGACCCUGGACAGGGACCUGCUGCGGCACUCGCCGCUGCUCCGCCACCUGGACCUGUCCAUCAACGGCCUGGCCCAGUUGCCCCCUGGUCUUUUCGACGGGCUCCUGGCUCUGCGCUCCCUCUCGCUUCGCUCCAACCGUCUGCAGAAUCUGGACCGGCUGACAUUUGAACCCCUAGCAAACCUGCAGCUGCUGCAGGUCGGGGAUAACCCCUGGGAGUGUGACUGUAACCUGCGUGAGUUCAAACACUGGAUGGAGUGGUUCUCCUACCGAGGGGGACGCUUGGACCAGCUUGCCUGCACCCUGCCCAAGGAGCUGAGGGGGAAGGACAUGCGGAUGGUCCCCAUGGAGAUGUUCAACUACUGCUCCCAGCUGGAGGACGAGAAUAGCUCAGCUGGGCUGGAUAUUCCUGGGCCACCCUGCACCAAGGCCAGUCCAGAGCCUGCUAAGCCCAAGCCCGGGGCUGAGCCGGAGCCGGAGCCCAGCACAGCCUGCCCACAGAAGCAGAGGCACCGGCCGGCGAGCGUGAGGCGAGCCAUGGGCACGGUGAUCAUUGCAGGGGUCGUGUGCGGCGUCGUCUGCAUCAUGAUGGUGGUGGCCGCUGCCUAUGGCUGCAUCUACGCCUCCCUCAUGGCCAAGUACCACCGGGAGCUCAAAAAGCGCCAGCCCCUGAUGGGGGACCCCGAGGGCGAGCACGAGGACCAGAAGCAGAUCUCUUCUGUGGCCUGAGCGCCCAUCCCCACCCGGCCAGGUAGGAAGGGCGGGGAGAGCACACGGCAUUGCUCAGCCACAGCUCCCACCUUGACCCGGCGCUGGCCACUGCCUCCCCGAGUCCACCCUCCUCCCCGCCCUCCAGCAGACAAGCCACACCGGGUUCUCUCCCUGCACUUUCGAGGCUCCCUGAAAGCCACCGUGCUGGGGGCUCCUGCUGAUGCUCCUGUCUGGGCCAGUAAAUCUUUGGAACAUGUGGGGGAUCUCCCUAAGCUCUGGCCACAGCAAAGCAAGGAGGUGUGUGCAAGAGGAGGCUUCCGGACUGGGCAUUCCCCUGUCGCCCUUCCUGCCCUGGGGUGGCCAUAGCUGGUGACUCUUCCUACCUUGCUGGUCCCACCUCACCUGCAUUGAGGGGACGGGGAGGGAGGGAUCUGAGGGAUGAAGGUAGAUUUCUGAGACUCUCUCCUAAGCCAGAAAGACGUUCUUAACACCCCUGCAGUGUGAAAGCUGGUCCAGCUCUACAACUGUUGGUACCAAUGUGCAAACACACCAGCCCUGCCAUCUGGACCCAGCACUCAGAAACACCAUACACCCCUGGCCGACGCCAUCAUGCCCCUGGAUCUGCUAUAGGCCACACUGACCACAUGCUCCUGGAUUCGCUAAUUCACUCACACACCCAUUGCAUCACCAGUGCGGUCACAUGGAUUGAAAGAAUUAAUACACACACACACACACACACACUCACACGGUCACACGGAGACCGAGGCUAUGAGCGCUCGAACAGCAGAGACAUGCUCUUCCCCAGGGGUCUCCCUGAGACCACAGAGCCUCUCGCGUGCUCACUGCAAUCUUCUCAAGUCAACAGCAGGAAGGAACUCAACCAGUAACACCAGGAUCCUUUGAGAUCCUCUAAAGUGGGCCAAAGUGGUGCCCCUGGAGGAGCCCUCCUGUCACCAUGGUAACCCUCUCACACCUCUCCUGCUGGGCUUUCCCGGGAUACCACCCAGGGGCCUGGAGCGGCUGCAUGUGUGCAUGGCGGCCUCCUGAGGACCCAGCCACACACCACUGGUGUUGCCUCGGUCCUGCCCACGCAUCUCACAGCACCAGGCCCUGUGGGGCCCCCACUGAUUCCUCCACAGCCUGCAGCCUGGCACCGUGACUCUGUGCCUCUCGCCCUCCAUCUUCAGUACUCCUGGCCUGUGACUUCAGGGCUGGGACUUGGUGGUGCUUUGCCAUUGGUGGCACCCUCUGGGGAAAGCAGGUGGCAGGCAGAGAACACGGUGGCUCCCCUGAGGCUCAUUGCCUGCCAGCUUAUUGCAGACAGAGCCCAGGAGCAGGAGCGGGUGGCCACGUGCUGCCCAGAGGCUCCCAGGAUGGGGCCUCUGUUCCCGGGCUUUGUCUGCUCAGUGUGGCUCCCUAGAGCACCCAGCCGGGGCCAAACCAGAGAGUGGGUGGGGAGCCUGUCUGGGACAGAGCCACCUGCUGCCAAGGCAGUGCAAGUUUUCCAGGUUACCUGUCCCCCUCCCUAGCUCUGCCCCUCCUCAGAGUGUGAAGAUGGUGGGUACCUAGGUGUCAUGCUCACAGGCUCAGGAGGCAUCAGGCUCGUCCCUGGCUCUGGGAUGGAAUCUCGAUGGGGGCUCAGGAAGAGGCCAGCAAGAACCCUGAAGCCAAGGGUCUGAGCAGAGGGAGUUGGCAGGCCUAGCUCCUGUGCCCCACUCCGACCCUCCCUGCUCAUGCGGCAGUGGGUGGGUGAGGUGGGCUGGGGGCCUGGAGGAGUGCCUUUGAGGAGGUCAGUCCUGGCAGGUGGACAGAGGACGCCUGGCAUGGGCUGCUUACUGGGACCCCAGGCGGCCCUGGCCAUGGCCACAGUCUUCCUUCUUUUGGCGUGUGGGCUGGUACCAGAUCUGGGGAUUUUCUAAAGGGACUGGGGGGAGGGGAGGGCAUUGUCAAUGGUGGUAUCUUUAGCCUGAGACAGAAGAUUUUUAAAGGCAAAAUUAUAUUUCUGGUUUGUUGUUUCAGAAGACCAAUAAAGACUGUAUUUUCCUAUGUA